AUUCCUGCGCUGGAGGCCGCCUCUGACGCCACCGGCUGGGCUCCGCCAUGAGUUCGGCGCCGGCCUCAGGCUCCGUGCGCGCGCGCUAUCUUGUGUACUUCCAGUACGUGGGCACCGACUUUAACGGGGUCGCGGCCGUCAGGGGCACUCAGCGCGCCGUCGGGGUCCAGAACUACCUGGAGGAGGCCGCCGAGCGGCUGAAUUCCGUGGAGCCGGUCAGGUUCACCAUCUCCAGCCGCACGGACGCCGGGGUCCACGCCCUGAGCAACGCGGCGCACCUGGACGUCCAGCGCCGCUCAGGCCGGCCGCCCUUCCCGCCCGAGGUCCUGGCCGAGGCCCUCAACACACACCUGCGGCACCCGGCCAUCAGGGUCCUGCGGGCCUUCCGAGUGCCCAGCGACUUCCACGCUCGUCACGCAGCCACGUCCCGGACCUACCUGUACCGCCUGGCCACUGGCUGUCACCGGCGUGAUGAGCUGCCGGUGUUUGAACGCAACCUAUGCUGGACUCUCCCGGCAGACUGCCUGGAUAUGGUCGCCAUGCAGGAAGCCGCCCAGCACCUCCUCGGCACACACGACUUCAGCGCCUUCCAGUCCGCUGGCAGCCCGGUGCCGAGCCCCGUGCGAACGCUGCGCCGGGUCUCCGUUUCCCCAGGCCAAGCCAGCCCCUUGGUCACCCCCGAGGAGAGCAGGAAGCUGCGGUUCUGGAACCUGGAGUUUGAGAGCCAGUCUUUCCUGUAUAGACAGGUACGGAGGAUGACGGCUGUGCUGGUGGGUCACGGGCGGCUCUGGGUCACAGGUGGCUCUGGGUCACAGGUACGGAGGAUGACGGCUGUGCUGGUGGCCGUGGGGCUGGGGGCUUUGGCACCUGCCCAGGUGAAGACGAUUCUGGAGAGCCAAGAUCCCCUGGGCAAGCACCAGACACGUGUAGCCCCAGCCCACGGCUUAUUCCUCAAGUCAGUGCUGUACGGGAACCUCGGUGCUGCCUCCUGCACCCUGCAGGGGCCACAGUUCGGGAGCCACGGAUGACCCUGGACACUCAAGCCAAAGUUAGGCCACACCAGGCCCAACCCUGUGCUGGUCAAGCCAGGGCAGUCACAGCUGCUUGGGGCCCACAGCACUGCUGCCUGGUCUCCACAGUAGCCUCCCUGCCCGGGUCCCAGCACCCUGGAUGCCCGUCUCUGUCCCAGGCGGGAUGGGGCACAGUGCAGGACACAGCCAUGUACACCAAGAAGAGAGUACCAAGUAGUCUUUUGUUCAGCUUUUACUGGAAACUGCUGUCUAGGACCACCUGCCCUAACCAGGAAUAAAGGCAAGACAGCCUGGA